AGUGGGACGCCAAGACUGGAGAGGAAGCGACUGCGGGGAGUAUUUCCAUUUUAACCGGAAACAAUCCCUGAACCCACAGGAAUGAAUGCCUAAUGGUGGAGUUUCAGCCAUCAGUGACAGGCUGAACCCAGACUCCCAGGGCACCUGCUUGCACCUUUGAAUGAUGGCCUGAACUAUGAACAAACGGGACUAUAUGAACACUUCGGUACAGGAGCCCCCUCUUGACUACUCCUUCAGAAGCAUCCACGUCAUUCAAGAUCUGGUAAAUGAGGAGCCAAGGACAGGACUACGACCACUGAAGCGUUCAAAGUCGGGGAAAUCACUGACCCAGUCCCUGUGGCUGAAUAACAAUGUUCUCAAUGAUCUGAGAGACUUCAACCAGGUGGCUUCACAGCUGUUGGAGCACCCAGAGAACCUGGCCUGGAUCGACCUGUCCUUUAAUGACCUGACUUCCAUUGACCCUGUCCUAACAACUUUCUUCAACCUGAGUGUCCUCUAUCUUCACGGCAACAGCAUCCAGCGCCUGGGGGAGGUGAAUAAGCUGGCUGUCCUUCCUCGGCUCCGUAGCCUGACACUCCAUGGGAACCCCAUGGAGGAAGAGAAAGGGUAUAGCAGGCCCUGGACUCCCCGACCUGUCCUGUGCUCUGGUCCUCCAGCCCAGGGCCCAGGUAGGGACCAUGUCCCCUGCCAUUGCAUUGGCCUUCCUGCCACUGGUGGUAACAUUGCUGGUGCGGUACCGGCACUACUUCCGAUUGCUGGUGCGCACGGUCUUGCUGCGAAGCCUCCGAGACUGCCUGUCAGGGCUGCGGAUCGAGGAGCGGGCCUUCAGCUACGUGCUCACCCAUGCCCUGCCCGGUGACCCUGGUCACAUCCUCACCACCCUGGACCACUGGAGCAGCCGCUGCGAGUACUUGAGCCACAUGGGGCCUGUCAAAGGUCAGAUCCUGAUGCGGCUGGUGGAGGAGAAGGCCCCUGCUUGUGUGCUGGAAUUGGGAACCUACUGUGGAUACUCUACCCUGCUUAUUGCCCGAGCCCUGCCCCCUGGGGGUCGCCUUCUUACUGUGGAGCGGGACCCACGCACGGCAGCAGUGGCUGAAAAACUCAUCCGCCUGGCCGGCUUUGAUGAGCACAUGGUGGAGCUCAUCGUGGGCAGCUCAGAGGACGUGAUCCCGUGCCUACGCACCCAGUAUCAGCUGAGUCGGGCAGACCUGGUGCUCCUGGCACACCGGCCACGAUGUUACCUGAGGGACCUGCAGCUGCUGGAGGCCCAUGCCCUACUGCCAGCAGGUGCCACCGUGCUGGCUGACCAUGUGCUCUUCCCUGGUGCACCCCGCUUCUUGCAGUAUGCUAAGAGCUGUGGCCGCUACCGCUGCCGCCUCCACCACACUGGCCUUCCAGACUUCCCUGCCAUCAAGGAUGGAAUAGCUCAGCUCACCUAUGCUGGACCAGGCUGAGGUCCAGGCCCAGGGGUACUUACUGAUGCCCACCCCCACCCCCACCCAAGCAGGGACCUCAAAAUCCCCUCCCUUUCCUGUUUGGGGCCUUGACACACGCUGGGCUCAGGGCUAGGGAGUCUCUCUUCCCACCUCUGACCUCUUUCAGCCUCUACACUGACCUCAAGUGUCAAGUUCUAUCAGGCUGCUUGGUCUCACUAGGCCCCCUCUUUCCAGAGAGAACCAUGGACUGACAGCAAGAAGCCUGAGCUCCCGACCCAGCUCUGUCACUGAUUUGCUGAGUGACUCCAAGGGAAUCCCCACCUUGCUCUGAGAUUUAAUCUUCUCUCUUAACACGAAGGAAGCUGGAUGGGAGAGCUCCAGGGGCCUCCCAGUUCUCGGCCUCAGAAAGCCUCCCAUCCUCAGCCCAUGCCAUUCUGGGUGGGAUCAGAGGAAGUGGCAAUGAGUUAGACGCCCUGCAGGAAUAGCUGGAUGCAAGCUGGGCCAGAGAAAAUGGCACAGAACCCUGGACCCAGGGCCAGGGAUGCCCUGGCCUUCCCUAACUCUGGCCCACCUAGCCAAUUAGGUGUGGCUGAUGUCCCUUGAGUGCCCUCUUCCUAAAGCCCAAAAGAAGAUGCUGGACUCCUCUGGGCCCCACCAACAAAUAGGGAAUAGACAUGGGUGGAAAAUCACUCCUUUGUCUUUAUUAAAGAAACUUAGACCAGACCUGGCAAUCAAGGGGUGAGGUACUGGCCAGGAAGGUGGAGUAGGUUUCAGGCCCUGGGGAUUUCAAGUGCAGACUGAUGGCCUGGGAGGGGCCAAAGAGACCAGAUCCUGGCAGCAGCUGAGGAGGUGCCCAAGGGCACUUUCAGGCACUGGGGCCAUCAGCUGGUUCUGUGGGCAGGGGUUGGGGGUUGGGAUGCAGGGUAGUUUGGGCUGGCCUGGAAUCUCCCUGAGGCCACCCUGCCUUGUCUACCUAGAUCAUCCACUGGUCCUGAUCCUGUUCGUUGCCUUCCAUGUCCACCUGGAGAGGAGGCUGGGUGUGGGUGGGGAGGGGCCUCAGCCAGCCUCAGCCCCAGAUCCUGCCCCUGGCUGGAUCCAGGGUUUCUGUACCCCUUGGCCAUCAACUGGGUCAGGAGCAAGGGUCCAGGAACAGAGGCCCUCCCCCAUACCCCUUGCCUACCUCAUUGACCUCUCCAUCAUCCGGUGACUCAUUGUAGUCAUUCAUCUCGUCCAUGUCCUGCAUAUCCUCAUCAUCCUCUGAGUCCUCUUCACUAUCCUCAUCAUCUUCAUCAUCCUCUUCUUCCUCGUCAUCAUAGUGCUGGUGGGCAGGACAGAGCCUGUAAGCCCUACAGGCCUGCAUGGACCAGUUCAAGAACUGACCCACUUGAGCCUCUCUCUAGGGCCAAUGAAUGACCCCCUACCCCGACACUCCCUCCUUGAGUCUAGCAGGCUGGUGCAUGUUCUGCAGGACCUUAAUGCUAGGCCCAAUGCCCACCCCUUCUAUCUCCCCUUUUAGGCUUUUACCCAGAUCUGAGAACCACAACUGCUCUGGGUCAGAGACAGGACAUUCAGAAUUAGAGCAGAGCCUCGGUCCACUGCGGCCCCCACACAGGCCCCACCUGCUAGAGCCACUCACCUCUGAGGCUGGCUUGCCAAUAGGAACCAGGUUGUUGUCUUUCUCCGCGAUGCUUUGGAGCUGUGGGCAAAGGCACAGAGGAACAAGGCCAGAGCCCAAGUAGGGCAGGUCAGGGGCAUGGGACUGGCCCAUUCUGCCCAGAAGACAACCCACACGUGUUGGGGAGAAGCUUCCUCCCAGUUCUCAGGGAGAUACAAUCCCUUUCUUGUCAUCUGCCAUUUAUGAACUUGAUCCAAAUA